ACAUUUGCGGGAACGCAGAGCGGAGCGUGGAGAGCGGAGCGAAGCUGGAUAACAGGGUAAAGGGAGUGGGUGGGGGGCCUCUGUCCAGGGAGGGCGGCUCGGGUCGAGGACCAGGGUCCGGACUGGGAGCAAUGACGGGGAGCCUGCCUGACCUCUCGCUGGCCACAACUAUGCCCUGCACCUUGCGUGGGAUGUGCGCCACGUCUGUCUCUGUAAUUCCCCCUGGCAGGUCUGGGACCCCCCUGAGACUCCGUCAGAAGAUUCGGUCCUCCCCAUAGGUGGCUUUACCUCUAAGCAUCCCGCCCUCUUUUCCCCCAUCGCCCGCCCUUUUUGAGCCCGAAAGCUUGCAGCCAACUUCCAACUCCCUGUCCUGUCCUAGGGACCGAUGAUGUGGCGACCAUCAGUUCUGCUGCUUCUGUUGCUACUGAGGCACGGGGCCCAGGGGAAGCCAUCCCCAGACGCAGGCCCUCAUGGCCAGGGGAGGGUGCACCAGGCGGCCCCCCUGAGCGACGCUCCCCAUGAUGACGCCCACGGGAACUUCCAGUACGACCAUGAGGCUUUCCUGGGACGGGAAGUGGCCAAGGAAUUCGACCAACUCACCCCAGAGGAAAGCCAGGCCCGUCUGGGGCGGAUCGUGGACCGCAUGGACCGCGCGGGGGACGGCGACGGCUGGGUGUCGCUGGCCGAGCUUCGCGCGUGGAUCGCGCACACGCAGCAGCGGCACAUACGGGACUCGGUGAGCGCGGCCUGGGACACGUACGACACGGACCGCGACGGGCGUGUGGGUUGGGAGGAGCUGCGCAACGCCACCUAUGGCCACUACGCGCCCGGUGAAGAAUUUCAUGACGUGGAGGAUGCAGAGACCUACAAAAAGAUGCUGGCUCGGGACGAGCGGCGUUUCCGGGUGGCCGACCAGGAUGGGGACUCGAUGGCCACUCGAGAGGAGCUGACAGCCUUCCUGCACCCCGAGGAGUUCCCUCACAUGCGGGACAUCGUGAUUGCUCUGCCCGGAGCUAAAUUUCCAAGAGAACCUCUCACUCUUACCCCAGGGGUCCAGCCUCCCCCAGGAGCCAGGGUCAUCGGCCCCCAGCCUCAAUGCCCCUUUCUCCUCCAGGAAACCCUGGAGGACCUGGACAGAAACAAAGAUGGCUAUGUCCAGGUGGAGGAGUACAUCGCGGAUCUGUACUCAGCCGAGCCUGGGGAGGAGGAGCCGGCGUGGGUGCAGACGGAGAGGCAGCAGUUCCGGGACUUCCGGGAUCUGAACAAGGAUGGGCACCUGGAUGGGAGUGAGGUGGGCCACUGGGUGCUGCCCCCUGCCCAGGACCAGCCCCUGGUGGAAGCCAACCACCUGCUGCACGAGAGCGACACGGACAAGGAUGGGCGGCUGAGCAAAGCGGAAAUCCUGGGUAAUUGGAACAUGUUUGUGGGCAGUCAGGCCACCAACUAUGGCGAGGACCUGACCCGGCACCACGAUGAGCUGUGAGCACCGCGCACCUGCCACAGCCUCAGAGGCCCGCACAAUGACCGGAGGAGGGGCCGCUGUGGUCUGGCCCCCUCCCUGUCCAGGCCCCGCAGGAGGCAGAUGCAGUCCCAGGCAUCCUCCUGCCCCUGGGCUCUCAGGGACCCCCUGGGUCGGCUUCUGUCCCUGUCACACCCCCAACCCCAGGGAGGGGCUGUCAUAGUCCCAGAGGAUAAGCAAUACCUAUUUCUGACUGAGUCUCCCAGCCCAGACCCAGGGACCCUUGGCCCCAAGCUCAGCUCUAAGAACCGCCCCAACCCCUCCAGCUCCAAAUCUGAGCCUCCACCACAUAGACUGAAACUCCCCUGGCCCCAGCCCUCUCCUGCCUGGCCUGGCCUGGGACACCUCCUCUCUGCCAGGAGGCAAUAAAAGCCAGCGCCGGGA